AGAGCCAUCAUGUGAGUCAUAUGAAAGCUCCACGCUGCUGACCUCUGGCAAAAAGGGAGAGAACAAGGAUAGGAGAGGCAGUGGGGGAAAGGUUCAAGUGCGGGUUUUCUCCUUGAACCUACAAGAUUAUGGGUCAAGAGCUGUGUGCAAAGACUGUACAGCCUGGAUGCAGCUGCUACCAUUGUUCAGAGGGAGGCGAGGCACACAGCUGUCGGAGGAGUCAGCCUGAGACCACGGAGGCUGCGUUCAAGCUAACAGACCUAAAAGAAGCAUCAUGUUCCAUGACUUCAUUUCACCCCAGGGGACUUCAAGCUGCCCGUGCCCAGAAGUUCAAGAGUAAAAGGCCACGGAGUAACAGUGAUUGUUUUCAGGAAGAGGAUCUGAGGCAGGGUUUUCAGUGGAGGAAGAGCCUCCCUUUUGGGGCAGCCUCAUCUUACUUGAACUUGGAGAAGCUGGGUGAAGGCUCUUAUGCGACAGUUUACAAGGGGAUUAGCAGAAUAAAUGGACAACUAGUGGCUUUAAAAGUCAUCAGCAUGAAUGCAGAGGAAGGAGUCCCAUUUACAGCUAUCCGAGAAGCUUCUCUCCUGAAGGGUUUGAAACAUGCCAAUAUUGUGCUCCUGCAUGACAUAAUCCACACCAAAGAGACACUGACAUUCGUUUUUGAAUACAUGCACACAGACCUGGCCCAGUAUAUGUCUCAGCAUCCAGGAGGGCUUCAUCCUCAUAAUGUCAGACUUUUCAUGUUUCAACUUUUGCGGGGCCUGGCGUACAUCCACCACCAACACGUUCUUCACAGGGACCUGAAACCUCAGAACUUACUCAUCAGUCACCUGGGAGAGCUCAAACUGGCUGAUUUUGGUCUUGCCCGGGCCAAGUCCAUUCCCAGCCAGACAUACUCUUCAGAAGUCGUGACCCUCUGGUACCGGCCCCCUGAUGCUUUGCUGGGAGCCACUGAAUAUUCCUCUGAGCUGGACAUAUGGGGUGCAGGCUGCAUCUUUAUUGAAAUGUUCCAGGGUCAACCUUUGUUUCCUGGGGUUUCCAACAUCCUUGAACAGCUGGAGAAAAUCUGGGAGGUGCUGGGAGUCCCUACAGAGGAUACUUGGCCGGGAGUCUCCAAGCUACCUAACUACAAUCCAGAAUGGUUCCCACUGCCUACGCCUCGAAGCCUUCAUGUUGUCUGGAACAGGCUGGGCAGGGUUCCUGAAGCUGAAGACCUGGCCUCCCAGAUGCUAAAAGGCUUUCCCAGAGACCGCGUCUCCGCCCAGGAAGCACUUGUUCAUGAUUAUUUCAGCGCCCUGCCAUCUCAGCUGUACCAGCUUCCUGAUGAGGAGUCUUUGUUUACAGUUUCAGGAGUGAGGCUAAAGCCAGAAAUGUGUGACCUUUUGGCCUCCUACCAGAAAGGUCACCACCCAGCCCAGUUUAGCAAAUGCUGGUGAAAAGAAAGGGCGAGAUCACCAAGGUUCUUCCAGGGCUGUAUUUCUGCAGUUUCGGUUUUCAUUUGCUUCAGCUUACUAAGAAGCUUCAAAUCUAACUCCAUACUGAACAAGGGGCUUUAUGUCCUCACCUAUGACCUGGAAUAGUUUAAAUAUGGUGUUCAAGGCAAUAGUACAUAAUAGUGGAAGAAAAUUCAGUGGAAGGUUAUUGCUAUUGUCAUUUGCAUAGAAUUUAAGUGAUUGAUUUAAAAAAACUGGACAUAAACUAAGUCUAAGAAGAGGGCUUCUGAAUAACUUCAUUCAUUUUGGCAUUUGUUAAGAGAUUCCUGGGCUAGAAGGUUGAUUUCCCAAAAAGACAGAUAAGAGACUGACAAUUUAAAAGAAUCUGGAGACAGAGCUGGUGCUUACAGAGACCUGCCACUCCUGUGUUCACUUACAAUUUCUCCCAACAAAAGGAUUUCUGUGGCAAGGAGAAAACUAGCCUAAAGUUUAGAAAAAGAUGGUUUCUUGGAUAACAUUGUUAACAAAAGGACUUCCUGAGGACUAUUUAUUAUUAUUUUGUAGGGGGCACUUCCUCCUUCACUAAACUGGAUUAUCAGAACGUAUUACCACCCAACCCAUAUUUUAGAAGUUUGGAUUUGGCUGCUGAUUAGAAAUGAAUUUCAGGCUAUCUCCUCCUACUGAAUCUUAAUUGUCUGUGAUGAUGGCAACAGUGAUGGGGAAUCUAAGCGCUGGUUUGAUGGUGGAGAUAUUGAAUAAGUAGUUGGGAGCAGAGUUCCAAAGAUGUAAUUUAAGCCCUGUUGCACCACCACACACACACACACACACACACACACACACACACACACACCCCUCAAGUAAAAUGAGAGAUCUGUCUUAGCUAACACGUGUGCCGUUUUAUACAAUGACUCCUUCUAAAAGCAGCCAGGGAAACUCAAAUCGCUUCUGUCCAGGGAUCAUCUCAGGAAAUGUAGCAGCCUAGAAACCAGAGACCUCUGUAUAUCCUUUGGAAGAGCAAGGAGGAACUAAUUAAGAGAUAAUUAAAAAAUAGUAACUAUCCCCCAAUGUCUGAGAUGGAAAAAGGAAAAAGACACAUGGGUAGCCCAAAUCAACCUGCCUGAGUAAGUAUCUGAUUUUAGUAAGGCAUUUGACAAAGACUGUCCAGCUAUACCUGAAAGAUGAAACAGUGUAGGCUGGGUGAUGGAGCAGAUAUAUGUACUCAAAUCAUGGUGUUUAUUUAACCCAGAGAAAGGCCAGCCGUGGUGUGCUACAAGGUUCAGUCUUGAGUCCUAUUCUGGUCAAAUAUUUUUAUUAAUUACUCGAAUAAAUCAGAGUACAUGGACAACUUUAUACAACUCCUUGAAGUAAGUACUAUUAUUAUUAAUUUAUGACUUCCAUUUCACAAAAGAGGAGACUGAGGCUCAGUGAAGUUAGGUAACUCCUUCAUAGUAGCAUGCCAGAGUGAAGAUGCAAACCUCAGACCUGGUUCUCCAAUGUUCCUGACACCUAUCGAAUUUAGAGAAUACACAACUCUUGCAGAGGCAGCUGCUAUUUAGUAUUGGAUCAUGAUUCAAAAGACACCUUGCUAGAAGCCAAUGAACAGCAGGCCAAAACAACACUUACUUGCAUCAAAUUUCAUCUGACUUAAAUUCUUACACUUUGGGCUACAACUUAAAAAAGGCUAUGACUUAGUGGAAAUUGGCACUUUUAAGUACAAUAUGAAUUAAUAGUAUAAUUUCGCUGUCCCCCAGAGAUAAUGCUAGUACCAAUCGAAAGCUCAGGGAUGCUACUGUUGACGCAUCAGCAAGAGUUCUUGAGCAGUUUUACCUGUCCAUCAAUACAAAGAGUUCCCACAACAGUAGUGGGAUUCCUCUGCCUCUCUGAAGAUAUGAGAGCUAUAGGAGGGAUUCCCAUGUUGGAGGUUAGAAGAGCUGACCUCCAAUGUCCCGUCUAAUUCCAAGAUUCUCCAAUAAUGACUUUGGAACAGCUGUGUACAGAUUAUACUUGGAAUUAUGCUUAGAUACUAUUGCUGCAGGAAUGAAUAGACAAAUUUUGUUAUUAAAAAAUUGAUUUUAUUAAGUGGAAGUUGACAGAAUUAUCCUCUUUAUAAUGGAGGAACAUUAUGCUUAUGCAUAUGCAUAUACCUUAUGCAUAUGAUUAUGCUUGUGCUUCCUUCUUUAAUGGAUUUACCUAUUCAAAAGCUUAAUAAAUGUUAUAAGACUCUAAAACAUUUAAAUCUUUCAUUUCUCAAUUUUAUCAAAUAAACAUUCCUGGAAUUUGUGCAUA